AGGGUGUGCGCACUCCUGGGUAGAGCUGGGAGCCGCCUGCUAGCUGGCGCCUCGUAUUUUCCUUGGCAACCCGCUACCCAGCCCCAACCUGGGCGGCUGCAGCUCUGAAGACACGAGAGAGGGUACUUGGUUUGGGUUUGAAAAGGGAAGAGCGGUCUUGUAUGCAGUAGUCUGGCCGGACCGACACUGAGAGGCCCAGGUGUUUGGAAAGCAGGAAAGAGGAGGCCAGGGUAAGCAGCUACUGAUAAAGAGCCCUUGUUCUCACCUUCAACCCUGUCCCCUCCCCCCCAGUACACCCCCCAGGGAUCCCUCCCCAUUUAGCUGGAAGGUGGUGCUGCAAGGAGGGUCCUGCCCACCAAACACGGCCUUUAACUUUUUGGUGGUCCUGGCACCCCUUGCUCCAGGUUUUGGAGACCUGGUGCCAGAGUGGGGAGAGUGGGCAGGCUGUCACCCAACUCCCAGCCCAGGCCAGGCUGACUCACGCGGUGACCAGAGCCAUCAGGAGAGGGAGGCAGGCCAGGCUGUCUCCAGCCAGCCCUGUGAAGAGGAAGAGCGAAAACAGGGAAUUAGUUUGAAACUUAAACUGUUGUGAACUAGGGGGGUGAAAGGGCCGCAAAGCCAGCUGAUCUGACAUGGAGCCGCAUACCUUGGGGAUUAAGUAAAUAUGUACUGUAGAAAACCAAACCUGCAUGUAAUUCCAGGUUGCUUUUGUUUUGUUAAAUACUGCCCUGAGAUUUACAAUUCCUCCGGGGUGGCUCUGACUGGGACUGAACUUUGGAGCCUGAACUAUCAGCCAAAGCCGAUCCGAUUAACUCUUCCCUAGCCGGGCUGGCCGGAGCCUGUGGUGGCCAAGCUAGCAGGGGUCUGGCUGUCCAGGACUCCCUCUUCUCCUUGGGUGGUUUGGACAGCCGCUUGACCUUGCAUUUGGAGGGGGAGUUGGGAAGCGUUUUUAACCCUUGGACACAACGAAUAAGGGGAAGUCAGAGUUGUUCUCAGCAGUUUCAUUUCCUUGAGGCGAUGCCCCAUAAAAGGGCUCCUGAAGCUCUUUGUGAAGGGGACUGAAAAGGGCAGAUGAGGGUGUCCUUUGGGGCGGACGUGGGGUUUGGGACAAUUGCAUGUGAUUGUCAUUCUUUAGCUGUCUGCAUCCCACAGAAACUUUUUUCUGAGUCUUCCAGCUGGCCCAAGUCCUGGGUCUCUUUUACUGUUCUUGUAGCUGACUACAGUAGGCAGAUGAGGAACUCUUAGUCAAUCUGGAAAAACUCGACUGACUAUAAACAAUCCUAAAUUGAAAGAAGUGUAUGGCAUUGGGGGGUGGGUGUGAUAGUACAGAGUGGAGCCUGCAAGUUCACGCACCGGGAACCAAACCCCACCUAACUUGGACUGGACGUCCUCUUCCAGGGAAUCCAGCCAGGGCCAAUUAGAAAUGUGUCUUAAAUUGGUGUCAGGGUCACCAAAAACAAAAACAGGAUCCAUGGGGGCCUGUGAAACUUCGAGUGCCAUUCAUGCUCGGUUCAGUCAUCUGACUUGUCAGGAUGACCAGCAGUGCUCCCUGUAACUCGCCAUUAUCUGACCAAUUACUGGAGCUACUUUAUAAUGAGGCUUCUGGAGCUACUUUAUAAUGAGGCUUCUGGAGCUACUUUAUAAUGAGGCUUCUGUUUGCUGUCAUGGUGGGGAGUUUGGAAUUGUGGCUUCUUGCCUAACACCAAUGAGAGGACUUUGGGACAAACCCCCAGAGCCAGGAGUGUUUUGAGGCCUAGUGGGGUUGGGAACAAAGGGUCAAGUGUCGAGGGAGUGGGGAAAUUAUGGGUUGGGGACAGGUGUGAACAGUGGGCUUGGGGGUGGCCCAAGAGUACUAGACCAGAGAGGUCCAGUGCCACCCGCAGCCUGCAGUGAUACUAGACAGGGGGCGGCUGUGUGGAACCACAGAUGACAUCCCUUCUCCUCUUGAUGGAAGUGGAGGCUGCAUCUGAGAGCUUCCCAGCCUAGAUUCUGGUGGCUGCAUCUGAGAGCUUCCCAGCCUAGAUUCUGGUGGGACUGGAUCUGGGAGGGGGAAGACCCCAAAAAGCAAAAAAAAAAAAAAAAAAAAAGUGUACCAGAGUCUCUGCAAAGAGCUGACGUGUCCAGGAGUUAUCUGUUUAUUUGGGAAGGAGGGAGAGAGUUGACAACCCAGUUUCCCAUAAUGACCUUGAGUUAAAUAGGAUUUGGCAAUAUUUGUGGGUGGUGGUGAGCCUUAGGGUGCAAAGGUGGCCCAAAUAAGCGAGGGUUUUUUUUUUUUUAAAGGCACACUAAGGCUGUAAGAAUUUGAAAGCUCCGGACACAUCUCUCCUUACCCACAGUGCACUGUGGCAAACUGAGGCAGGGCCAGUCAUGGUUAGGGUUUCUAGGCGUAAAGGUCUUGCUUUUUAAUUUUCUUUGCCCUCCUAGAAUUCCUUCCACAAAAGCAUUCACAAACCUUAAACUUAUUCCCCUUCCCUCCAAGGGAACUAACUUCUGGCUAGUGGUCAGCCCCGGCUCCAGUCUUUGAGUUUGACAUGGUGUUAGCAGGAGCCCCUGAGAGGAGAAGUGGACCGUUCAUUUAGAAGUAUUUGUAGGGACCAUCCCCGCCUUUGGUCUGGUAUCCAGCAAGUGGCUGGACGAAAGUCUUGGGCCAUGAUUGCAAACCUUGGGAGGUGGGGCAACAUACGUGGGCCUAAUACCACGUCAGGAACUCCAGGACCUUGGCUGGGAGCAGUGGCUCAUGCCUGUAAUCCCAGCACUUUGGGAGGCUGAGGCAGGCGGAUCACUUGAGGUCAGGAGUUCGAGACCAGCCUGGCCAACAUGGUGACUCCCCAUCUCGACUAAAAAUACAAAAAAUUAUCCAGGCCUGGUGGUAAGCGCCCGUAAUCCCAGCUACUCGGGAGGCUGAGGCAGGAGAAGUGCUUGAACCCAGGAGGUAGAGGUUGCAGUGAGCCUAGAUCACGCCAUUGCACUCCAGCCUGGGCGACAGAGCAAAACUCUGUCUCAAAAACAAACAAACAAACAAAAAAACUCAAUUCCCACUUCCGAGAGGUAGUCUGAGGGGAGGUAUUUCAGGAAGGUAGUAUGGGAACUGGCUUGGAGUUCUGUCUUGCUGUCAGUGAAUUUACAGCAUGUGGGUAGAUAGCCCUGUUCCUACAGCACCCAGCCAGGAACUAGCACUGUGAGUAGAUUUAUGAACCCCAUUCUCCAGCACUUCCAUUCAGCAAGUCCUGUGUCCUUCCCAUCCCUAGCCCUGGGGCCAGCCCAAGCUUAUAAGUCCCUUGACACCAUCUCUGAGAGACCUAGCUUAGCAAACCUACCUGGGGUAUCUGUUCGGUGUUUGGCACAGCUCUGGGCCUGUAAGAAAAUGUAGCAAAGAUGAAUAAAGACCUAGAGUGUGGCCAGGUGCUUACAGUGAAGGCACAAGUCACCAUCUGUAUGUGCUUCCUGUGGUUACCAUGACCAAUUAGGACAAACUUGACGGCUUACUACAACAAAAUGUAUUCUCUUGUGGUUCUGGAGGCCAGAAGUCUGAAAUCAAGGCAUCAGCAGGGUUCUGGGUUCCUCUCCACUCAAAAGACUACGGGAAGAUCCUUCGUCAUCUCUUCCAGCUCCUGGUGGCUCCUGAUGCUCCUUGGCUUAUGGAAGCAUGGCUCCAGUCUCUCCUUUCAUCAUCCCAUGGCCUUCCUUGCUGUGUGUGUCUACGUCCCGUCAUCUCCUUUUUUUUUUUUUGAAACAGAGUUUUGCUCUUAUUGCCCAGGCUGGAGUGCAAUGGCGUGAUCUUGGCUCACUGCAACCUCCGCCUCCCAGAUUCAAGCGAUUCUCCUGUCUCAGCCUUCCGAGUAGCUGGGAUUACAGGCGUGCGUGCCACCAUGCCCAACUCAUUUUGUAUUUUUAGUAGAGAUGGGGUUUCUCCAUGUUGGUCAGGCUGGUCUCGAACUCCCAACCUCAGGUGAUCCACCUGCCUCAGCCUCCCGAAGUGCUCGGAUUACAGGUGUGAGCCACCGUGCCCACCCCCAUCAUCUUCUUAUAAGGACACUAGUUAUUGGAUUCAGGGCACACACUAAAUCCAAUGUGAUUGCAUCUCAAGAUCCUUAACUAGUUAUAGCUCCAAAAACUCUCUUUCCAAAUGAGGUGACAUUCUGAAGUUCUGGAUGGGCGUGAAGUUUGGGAGAUGCUACACAGUGGAAGCACAGAGGAGCAGUUAAUUUAUAGCAGGUGCUCAUGAAAGGUUUCAUGAAGGAAGGAGCAUUCGACUGAGCCUUGAAGAAGGUCAAGUGUUUCAACCAGAAGGGGUGUGACAAGGGAAAUCUAGGUACAAGAAACCACCUGAUCAAAAGCUCUACCUGGCUGGAAUUGCGGGAGGGAAGAGGAAAGGGAAGCAAGAAAACAUUGUAUUGUGGGAUAGGGAGGUAAGCAGGGAGUUUACACCUCAGACUCUGAGUCAGGUCAGUACUGGUGAGAAUAGAAAAAAAGAGAAAGAGAAGAGAAGGGUCCAGACAGGUCAUCUGUGGGUCCCUAGAGUCAUCAGGCCAAAACAGCUGCACUAACCAAUUUACAGGGAGAGAGCAGUGGCCCAUCUCUCCCAUCCUCACUCUGUGCAGCCUGAAAGCAGGCAGGUAGGCUACCUGUCCUACCUGUGACAUCUGGAAGUGUUUCUGCUUAGAGCAUCGGUCACAACUGACCUUACAAAUGAGCCUGUCUCAUGAAUAAACAAACAUCUCCUUCUUACUCCCCCAGGCCCUUCCCUUGGGGGAACAAAGGUGUCUACCUCUGGGACCACGCCCCCCUGCAGUCUUGCUCACUUGUGCAGGAGGCCAGAGACUGAGCUUUUAUUUAUUUAUUUAUUUAUUUAUUUUAAAAAUAGAGACGGGAGUCUCCCUAUGUUGCUUAGGUUAGUCUCGAACUCUUGGGCUCAAGCAAUCCUUCCUUCUUGACCUUCCAAAGUGCUGGGAUUACAGGUAUGAGCUUCCACACCCAGCCAAGACUGGGUUCUUGACCCUGGAAAAGUUACUACCUUCUCCAGGUUGCAGCUGAGAAGCACACCUAUAAAAUGAGAGGGGUUACAAUGAUCCCUAAGAUCCCGGCACGCUCAAAAAUUCUCGUCUUACACAUCAGUCAACCCAAGAAAGCAACGGAUUGCCAGGCUUCCCUGAAUUGCAAGCAGGAGACUUCCAGGUGAAGAAAGCAUUUGUCCCCAUCACUGAUCUCAGCCUUUGCUAGUCAUCAGAUGCCACCAAAUGAAAAAGAAGCAACUCAGAGUUGGAAGAUGUGCUGUGCCCCAGCUCCGCAGAGCCCCACACCCAUUCAAAACUCCCUCAACAGGUAGCUGUCUGCCAUGGAUUUAUUUCAGCUCUUGCAGAAGACGUUAGUAUUUCCAAACUGUCGCUUCUAAAGGAAUAAGGGACCCAAAUUCCCUGACUAGCAUGUCAAACAAAAUUUCCUGGUUUUUUUCUUCUAAAUUCACCAACUUUUCUAUUUGGGCUUUCAGGAAUGCCUCCUCCAUCUAGCAAUACUGACUCUGAGUCAAGUUCAUUUUCAGUGCACCCAGCCCUUCUGCUAAUUCUCAUUUCGACUUCAAGCUCUUCUGAGCUUCCAUCUUUUCAGAUGAAGCGCACUUGUUUAUGGCUGCACAGAUCCCUUCCAAGCCCUUCUGAUCUCUGUAUCUUUGCAGUUACUUUCUCUGGUUCAUUUCCAUCUUGGUAUUUGCCGAGGCCGUCUGCCUUGAGAAAGUGAUCUCGGCUGUAUUUAUGAGGUGUCCUUUCUAACCAGGAAGUGUAUCUGGUUGUCACAAUCGCUGUAACAAAAGCCCUUGUCUUAACCUGCCACUACCAGCGAUAUCCUACCACAGUUUUGAGCAUCAGUGCGGGAUGGGUCCCACACCCUACACGUUCUCCCUUAUCCUUGGACAAAAGCAUGAACACACCCAGAAUUUUAUAAGGCUGUGCUCACCGUUGUCUUCAGGAGACACAAUCCAAAAAUAUAAGUCCAUAAGAUACUUGAAACAUUUCAAACAUAUUAUUCAGAUGAACCACGAGGAUUACGAAACCAUUGAAGCCCAUUGGAAAUGAGAAAAGUGAGUCUAUUUAGACACUAGCAUGCCCAAAUGUGUGCUCAUUGCUGUGGCACCCCUGAAAUGAGUGAGAUCUUAGAAUCUGAAAAUGAGCACAUGCCUAGAUUCUCAACAAGAAAGUGCCGGGUUAGCAAAUGAAUGAAUGGUUGGUGGGAACUCAUUCAUUUAUUCACUUAUUCAUACAUUCAGCACAUUUACUGAGCACCUACUAUAUGCCAGGCACUGUUCUGGGCACUGAAGGCAUGCAGGGAGCAAAGCAGAUGAAAAUCCCCACCCAUGUAGUGAGAGCUGGCAUUUUAGUAAGAGAGACAGAUAAAAAGCAAGAUCAGUAGAACAGUACAUUCUCAUGCCUGUAAUCCCAGCACUUUAGGAGGCUAAGGCAGGCGGAACACUUGAGGUCAGGAGUUCAAGACCAGCUUGACCCAACAUGGUGAAACCCUCCUUCUCUACUAAUAAUACAAAAAAAAAAAAAAAAUUGCUGGGCAUGGUAGAGCGCACUUAUAAUCCCAGCUACUUGGGAGUCUGAGGCACGAGAAUUGCUUGAACCUGGGAGGCGGAGGUUGCAGUGAGCAGAGAUCAUGCCACUGCACUCCAGCCUGAGCAACAGUGGGAGACUCUGUCUCAAAAAAUAAAUAAAUAAAUAAAACAGAACAUUGAAUUGUCAUUAUAAGCAAUGAGGAGAAAACCAAUGAGGCAAGAAGGAUGGGAAUGCGAGGGCCUGAGAUUCUAGGUAGGGUAUAAGGAAGGCCACACUGAGAAGGAGACACGAGGAAAGACCUGAAGGAGGCGAGGGCAUGGUGGGAAGGGAGCAGUAGCAUUCCAGGAAGAGGACAGGGCAAGGGCUCUGAGGAGAGAGUGGAGUGUCUGAGGACCAAGAGGUGGCCAGUGUGGCUGAAGCAGUGAGUGAGUGGGGAGGAAGAACUGAGGGAGACAGGUUCCCAUGUAGGACAGGUAGACCUAGCUGGCCCCACGACUCAAGCAUCAUGCCCUCACCCAAGCCUUAGCAGGAUCCCCUGGCUGCUGUGACAGGCAGGUGGUGGAGGUGUCAGGCCAGGGGUGGGGGACCUGCUAGGAGGCCGCCAGGUUUCCAUGCCUCCUCCAAAAAUAUCACCCAGACUUGCUUCGCCACCUUCUUUGAGAGCUUCCCAGAGCUCAGGGAAUGCUGUCAGCAUUGCACUAGAGUUUUGGAGGAUGCUGAGGGCCUCCUCUGAUAUCUUUUACUGUCAAGAUGGAAGUGUCUGGGCUGAGGGUAAUGGAGAAUCUAGGCAGUCCGGGGUGCCACUGUUGGAGGGGGUGGGAGGCAGCUGGCACCCAGCCCUCAGGGCUCUGCUGGGCAGCCCUGCUCCCAGCCAGAUCCUGAUCUUUCUUGCUGGUAACUUAGGUGAGGAAGUGACAACCAGCUUCAGGGUGACACGGCUCUGAGGAAUCGUGACUAUGUUGGCUCUGUUCAUUGAUUCAGCAAACUAGGCCUUGGAGAUGCGGCAGGGAACCUCAUAAACAAGGUUCUCUCCUUGUGACACUUAGUGUUCUUGGAGUGACCACCAUCCCCAGACUGAAAAAUCUCCUAACACUGUGGAAGGAUGAGUUGGCACCAACAAGCAGGCUUCUAAUGGCAGUAGUGCUUAACCCCUCUGAAUAAAAUCAGAUAAUUGUGCUGGUGCUUAGAAUGAAGGAGAUGCUUUUCAGUCCUACUUUGUCAAACGACUUCUGGGGUAUUGUGUCCAUGUGGGCCAGCACUUUGACAGGGCCCUUGACCAACUGGAAGGUAUCCAGGGAGCAGGCUGGGUGACAAGGGCUAGAAGCCAUGACUUAGGUUGGGUGGCAAAUCCAUGGGAGUAUAGUUGACUGCUUAAGAGGCAAGAGAGGGUAUCAGCUGCAUUCCAGUACCACAGAGGCAUGGGACCUGUUCUAGAUGGUUCUGGAGGCCCAUGCUAGGCCCGUGGGGAGGGCUCGAAAAUGCAGACCUGGGCCCUGCAAGAGGAACACCUUCCUGCCCUUUGGAACAGGUUGCUCUUUAAGCAAACAUGGUGUCGAGAUUUCUGCACUGGGGGAGGUUAGGUUCUGGACAACCUCCUAGGUCCCUUCUACCCUUUGAUUCUGUGAGUCAUUGUCAUGAAGUCAGUGAGGGCAAUGACACAGGCAGGGGCAGGGGCAGGGGGCAGGAGGAAAAGAGGACACCAGCAUCGAUCAACCAACACUUGAAAAUUAAAAGAAGGCAGCCCUUCUCAGCAUGACUUCAGCAGGAUCCUCCAGCAGUGAUGUCAUUCCUUUGUCCAGGCUUUCCAGGGUGCUGGGGAGCAGGGAGGAGGCAAGAGGGUGCAGGGUGGGCACAGACUCACAUCCUUCACUCAGGCUUAGAUUCCUGUGGCUUCUGAACUGGAUGCUGAUGGCUUCCUUGCGUUCCUAGUAAUAUUCAUGACCGUGGUACUCUACAUGUCUGUGGUACCAUACACGAUUGGUAAUAUACGUGACUGUGGUAAUAUACAAGGGGACUUCAAAAAGGUGGUGGAAAAUGGAAUUAAAGGAUGAAAAUAAAAAAUAUAGGCCAGGCACAGUGGCUCACUCCUGUAUUCCCAGCACUGUGGGAGGCCGAGGCGGGCAGAUCACUUGACGUCAGGAGUUCGAGACCAGCCUGUCCAACGGGAUGAGACCCCAUCUCUACUAAAAAUACAAAAAUUAUCUGGCAUGGUGGUGCAUGCCUGGGAUCCCAGCUACUCGGGAGACUGAGGCAGGAGAAUCACUUGAACCUGGGAGGUGGAGUUUGCAGUGAGUGGAGAUCGCACCACUGCACUUCAGCCUGGGCAACAGAGCAAGACUGCGUCUUUCUCCCUCUCUCCAUAUAUACACACACACACACAUACACACACACACAUAUACACAAAUAUAUAUAUUUUAUUUCUCAACAUAAACUUCAUCAAGUUACAAGACACUUUUGUAAGCGAUGAUACCAGCCAUCUAGUCCAUCCCUAAAUAACUGAGGGUCCUGAGAGUUCAGCCAUGUCAAUACAGUCUUUUUUUUUACAUCAUUAGCUGAAGAGAAAUGGAUGCCCUUUGUCUUAGUCCUUUCUCACAUUGCUAUAGAGAAAUAUUAGAGACUGAGUAAUUUAUAAAGGAAAGAAGUUUAAUUGACUCACAGUUACACAUGGCUGAGGAGGCCUCAGGAAACUUACCAUCAUGGCAGAAGGAGAAGGGGAAGCAAGGCACCUUCUUCACAAGGCAGCAGGAAGGAGAAUGAACUUAGAAGGAACUACCGAACACUUAUAAAACCAUCAGAUCACGUGAGAGCUCCCUCACUAUCAUGAGAACAGCAUAGAGGAAACUACUCCCAUGAUCCAAUUACGGCCACCUCAUCUCUCCCUUGGCAGAUGGGGAUUAUGGGGAUUAUAAUUCAAGAUGAGAUUUGGGUGGGGACACAAUGCUUAACUGUAUCACCCUUUAAAGAUUUUUUAAGAUUAAGAAACAAAAGGAAGUUAGAAACAGCCAAAUCAGGACUGUAAAGUGGAUGCCUAAUGAUUUCCCAUCAAAACCCUCACAAAAUUGUCCUUGUUUGAUGAGAGGAAUGAAUGCGAACCUUGUCUUAGUGGAGCAGGACCAUCUGGUGAGGCUUUCCUGGGUGUUUUUCUGUUAAAGUUUUGGCUAACUUUCUCAAAACACUCUCAUUAUAAGCAGAUAUUAUUGUUCUUGUCCCUCCAGAAACUUAACAAGCAAAAUGCCUUGAACAUCCCAAAAAAACUAUUGCCAUGACCUUUGCUCUUGGUCGGUCUGCUUUUGCUUUGACUGGGCCAUGUCCACCUCUUGGUAGCCAUUGCUUUGAUUGUGCUUUGUCUUCAGGAUUGUAGUGGUUAAUGCUUCAUCCUCUCUUACAGUUCUUUGAAGAAAUGCUUCAAGAUCUUGAUCCCACUUGUUUAAAAUUUUUGUUGAAAGCAGCUGGGCACGGUGGCUCACACCUGUAAUCCCAGCACUUUGGGAGGCUGAGGCGGGCGGAUCACCUGGUCGGGAGUUCAAGACCAGCCUGACCAACAUGGAGAAACCCCAUCUCUACUAAAAAUACAAAAAAAAAAAAUUAGCUUGGCAUGGUGGCACAUGCCUGUAAUCUCAGCUACUCGGGAGGCUGAGGCAGGAGAAUCGCUUGAACCCGGGAGGCGGAGGUUGCCGUGAGCCAAGAUCACGUCAUUGCACUCCAGCCUGGACAACAAGAGUGAAACUCGGUCUCAAAAAAAUAAAUAAAUAAAAUAAAAUAAAAUAAAAUUUUCAUUGAAAGCUUUGCUCUCAUCUGCACCUGAUCUGGAUGCAGUGGUUUUGGUGCCCAUCAAGUGGAAAGUUUGUUCAACUUUAAUUUUUCAGUCAGAAUUGUGUAUGCUGAACCAAUGGAGAUGUCUAUGGUAUUGGCUUUUUUUUUUUUUUUUUUGCUGUUAAUUGUCAGUCCUCUUCAGUUAGAGCACAAACAAGAUGAAUUUUUUCUUUCUAAUUUGAUGUGGAUGGUCUGGCACUUCAGGCUUUAUCUUCAACAUCAUCUCAUCCCUUCUUAACAAGUUAUCCAUUUAUUAACUACUGCUGAUUUCUAUUUUUUUUUUUUUUUUUUUGAGACAGAGUCUCACUCUGUCGCCAGGCUGGAGUGCAGUGACAUGAUCUCAGCUCACUGCAACCUCCGCCUCCUGGGUUCAAGCAAUUCUCCUGCCUCAGCCUCCCAAGUAGCUGGGACUACAGGCGCACGUCACCAUGCUGGCUAAUUUUUGUAUUUUUAGUAGAGACGGGAUUUCACCAUGUUGGCCAGGAUGAUCUCAGUCUCUUGACCUUGUGAUCCGCCUGCCUCGGCCUCCCAAAGUGCUGGGAUUACAGGUGUGAGGCACCGCACCUAGCCAACUGCUGAUUUCUUUAGGGCAUUGUCCCCAUAAACUUUUCAUAAAGUAUCAGUGAUUUCACCGUUCUUCCAUCUAAGCAAGCUUCACUGUAAAUUUGAUGUUUGUUCUUGCUUCAGUUUUAGGAGAAUUUAUGUUGCUCUGAUAGGAGUUCUUUUCAAACUGAUGUCUUAUCCUUCUUAGUGCCUCAAACUAGAUCCCAUUUAGUCAUGUUAUAACAAGUUAGUUAUUUUGGGGCAAAAAAAAUCUCAAAUAUAUGCCUAGUUUUUUCGUAAUACGCAUUUUCCUUGAACUUUUUGAAGACCCUUUGUACAUGAUUGUGGUAAAAGCAUGAAUGUAGGAAUAUACAUGGCACUAUUACUAUACAUGGUACUGUUAAUAUACAUGGGAAUAUACAUGGCACUAUUAAUAUACAGGGUGCUAUUAAUGACUAUGGUACUGUACAGGACAUGGUAUUGUACAUGACUAUGGUAAUAUACAAGAUAGAUACUGUAUAUGACCUUGGUAAUAUACAAGAUGGAUACUCUACAAGACCAUAUUAAUAUGCAAGAAUGAUACUGUACAUGACCAUGGUAAUAUACAAGAUUGAUACUGUACAUAACCGUGGUAAUAUACAAGACCUAUACUGUACAUGACCAUGGUAAUAUACAUGGCUGUGGCACUGUACAUGACUGUGACAAUGUGUGUGACGAUGGUAACACACGUGACUUGGUACUCUACAUGACUGCACAGUGCUUUUGCACAUUCAUUGUCUUCCUUGACCUUUUUUUUUUUUUUUUUUUGAGAUGGAGUUUUGCCAGUCGCGCAGGCUGGAGUGCAGUGGCACGAUCUCGGUUCAUUGCAACCUCCACCUCCUCCCGGGUUCAAACGAUUCUCCUGCCUCCGCCUCCCAGGUUCAAGUAAUUCUCCUGCCUCAGCCUCCCAAGUAGCUGGGAUUACAGGCAUGCGCCACCCCAGCUAAUUUUUGUAUUUUUAAUAUAGAUGGGGUUUCACCAUGUUGGCCAGGAUGGUCUCGAUCUCUUGACCUUGUGAUCCACCCGCCUCAGCCUCCCAAAGUGCGGGGAUUACAGGCGUGAGCCACCGCACCCGGCCAGCAGCACGCAUUUCUGAGAUCCAGGUGAAGUGGCCGUCCUGGGACACGUCGCUGAGGGCAGAUUCUGAACCCAGGUUUCCCAGCUUCAACACUCCAUCUUUUCCCACUGCAACAAAUAAUCUCAGCCUGGCCUGGCCUGCCUCAUUCAGGGUCAUGGAGAGGUCAAGAGACAAGCUGUUAAGUAAUGGGGCUUAGUACACAGAGGGUUCUGGAGAGAGCGGUGAUAAGCAGUGAAUGAGUCAACAGGAUGCGGGCAGGGAUGUAGUGAAAUCCGCUUUUACACAAACAUCAUUUAGAGCACUGAGUAGCAGUAUUUGCAUACAAUGAAUGGGAGACUUGCCAAAGGAAUAAAAUAGUCCUCAGUUAUCAGGGUUUCUUUUAAAGAGUAAACUGACAAGCAGGGUAAUAGCACAGUUGAAUUUCUUUCAUUUGACAACCAGUGUGACAUCUUAACAUGCAGAGACCCAGCUGCAGAGGAGAGAGUGAGUGACAGCUCCCUCCAGUUAAGCCCGAGGUCACUGAGCUCUGCGUGGCCUGAGAGCUUUGAUCACUGUAAAUUAAGGGAAAUCUUAGAAGACUUCUCGAAGGAGGUGGCAACUGAGGGGGUUGCAGGAACUCUCCAUUUUUCUGCUGGUUGUAGAGCCCUUCAAGGGUCUGAAGAAAAUAUGAACUCUAUCCCAGGAAGAAGGUGCAACUGAAAGUUUUGUACUUUUAAGGGGUCAUGUACCCCUGUCGCCUAUCCCAGACUCUGGGUUAAGAAGGCUUGGACUAGAUACAAUCAAAACCCAUCCAAGUCCUACAGGCUCAGAUGCAGGCUCAGGGCGAGAGCUCGUGUGAGAGGCAGGGAACGCCCUGGUAUCCUGUGACACUGAAGCCAGGGCAAGCUCAGGGUGGAGAGUACAGAUGUGUGGCUUGGUGCUUAAGGCCACCAAUGGUCAGCCUGGUGAAGGCCACUGGGCCCCAGCCUUUCUUACCUCAUUGGCCAUCCCUACUUCAAGGAAUGUGGCCUUAAAUCCUCUUUUCAGCAGCCUUUCGGGGAUUUUGAUGAGUGAAGCGUAUGAUGAUCUUGUCCACACUGAAACAGCCUCCUAGGGAACACGGUCUCCUGUCUGCGUCCCACCUCCCCCAACCACUUCUACCAGCCUCCAAGCCCCGCGGUCCCCAUGCGGACCUCAGCGCCAGCUGAGGUUCAAGGUCCAGGUUUUCAAACUGGGUUCCGGAGCACCCUAGAGGCCCCAAGAAGGUAGGGCCACGUGGGAGAUGGAGCAGGGAGGGUUCUGAGGGACCCCUCCUUCCUGCGGACCAGAUCAGUGUUGUCACUUCUGUUUUGUGGCUUACAAUUCCAUGUUAAGAUUUUGGUGUGCAUUUUGAAAGAAAGUCAUUGUUUUAAAGAAAGGAAAAAAAUAAGGCUUGAAAAUGAUGCUUCAAGGAAAUGACUCAGCCCGCUCCCUCUCCUCGAUGGACCCUUCUUGGAUUUGCUGGAUGUCCCCUCUUUAAUGACACCUCCACCUUUGGCUCUUUACUCCAAGGUGCUGUGGCUUCUGGACCAAAUGCCCUCUAGUUCGCUUGGGCUUUUGCCCCUCAGGAGAGGGACCCACACUCCCACCCCAGAUGUGUGGAACCCCUCCUGCCCUCAGCCUCGGCACCUCCUCUACCUCUGGGGUGCCCACAAGCUAGAAGCUCUGAAUGCCCAAGCGGGGCUGAGACAGCCUCUCCAAGGGGGACUCAGCCCAAAUCCAUCUGCCAGAAAGGACACAGGAGGCUUCUCCCUGGCCCUCCCUGCCUCCAAAGCACCCAUCCCUGGGAGAGUGUGCCUUGACAACCCCAGCCCCAAAGCCCAGACCUGGCCCAAAGGCAGUGUCACAGCAGCCAAAAUCUUUUGGGCGGUAGAGGCCGGCUCCGGCCAGAGCACUCAUGCAAUUUGUGGUGCCGGCCAGGGCUGCUGGAAACCAGUGCCUAAUGCUGUAGAUUAUGAGGGGCCUCCCAGUGACCUGCUGUGUGACCUUGGGCGAGCAACCCUCUCUGGGCUUUGGUUCCCUCAUCUGAAAAAUGAAGGUGUGGAAAUGUAGUGAAAAAGCUCCUAUCACCUCCUGGGUAAUGGCAAGAGCGUUUCCAAGAGACAACCACUCCUUCCAGGUGGGGCAAUGGCCCUGGGGGUGGGGGGCGGUGGAUACCCCCUGCUCCAGCCCUUCUCCUUCUGCAUAUUAGAGCAGAUGCUCAGCAGGACAUCAGAGAAAAAAGGCAAAAAACCCACUGGCCUGACUCAACCUUGGUUCUGGGACUCCCCCGGGAAGCAGAGAGUUGUGCCCCUGCCACAGAAGCCCUCAGGGGGAAUUGGAGACUUUGACCCUUUCUAGAAGUCUGUGGGAGGGAACCACUCCCUACAGGGAGUCUGGCCAUCUCCCUUCCACCCGAGGCCUCACCUCUGUUGAGAUGACCCGUGGCACAGCCCCUGUCUUCCCAGGCAGGGGCUGGUCCAACAUAGGCCUUUCUGCAACCCAGGGGCUGAGGCUGGUCAGGGGUACAGCCUCCUCUCUGGUCCUGGCUGCCCAACCCCCACAACCAUCCAACUUCCCCUGCACAAGGCAUUAGUCAUUUUGAUCUCUGCGUCCAAGUAGCUCAAUUGGUCAGGACCGGGCUGCGGUGAGGCCAAAGUCAGGGGUUACCAUAGCAACUCACCACGCUUUGUGGCUGCUUGUUGAUAUCCACAGGGGCAGGGGGCAUGCCCUCUCACUCACCAAGUAUCUGGCAACUGGCACAGUAUCUGGCCCACAGUAGAUACUUAAUAAAUGGUUGUUGCCUAAAUGAAUGCAUGACCGACCCAUUGUAGCUAGUUAGAGCCAGUGAUUACUGAGCACCUACUGUGUGCCAGGGACUGUUCUAAGCCCUGACACGUCACAAGGUCAUUUACUACUCGAAGUAACCUUCCAGCGUGGGUACCGUUAUCAUCUUCUUCUUACCAACAGGACUCUGAGAGUCAGUAACUUAGAAUCACACAGCUAGUAAAUGACCCAGCAGGAUUGGAACCCAGGGUGUCUGCUUGUAACCAAUGAGUCUUGCCUUUUGGUUGAUAGUUUCACGGAAGAGAUGGCAUUGAUGGCCCCUAGUGGAGUCCGUAGCCAGGCAGUCUAUAUGGGUCAAACAACAUCACCUCCAGCUUUCCCGAUGGGGGCUCUGGAGGUGUUCCUCAGAUUGGUUUAUUGACUCAUGGGACCAGAAGUCCCUGGGUAGGGCUGACUUUGGGCAUGUCUCCAGGGGCUCAGUGCUGUCAGGACUCAGGAGAGUUUCUCUCUCCCCUCACUUUGAGGCAGACCUCUCUGCCACGGGGCUGCUCACACCUGCCCCCUGCUGCUCGUAACGUAACCUUUCCAGCUCCCAUUCAAGUAGACAGACAGGUGUUCUUUGCCCAGAAGUCCUGGAAGGGUCCAGGAAUUGGGUCUCUCUGGCAGUGACUGGGUGAGCCUGAACCAAGGAAAUGGUGCUCUAUUUGGCCAGCUGUGGGUCAUGGCCAGACUCUGAGCCAGGGGUAUACCAGCCCCAGCCAAGCCAUAGGGUUUGGGAGUCGGGAGGUCGGCUUCUGCAGGGCAGAUGGGGGGAUACAAUGAGCAGGAGCAAGGGGUCCAGUACACCUUCUUGUGGAAGGACAACACUCAUCUUCCAGUCAUGCCACGUGGAAACAGCCAGGAGAGCCAGGCCUGCCUGUAUCAGGCAGCCCUCCAGAGCUAAUCCUGCAGACCUUAUCAGGUCAUUUACUGAUGCCUUACCACCGCGCCCCCCAACCCCCCACCCAUCUCCCCAAGAAAAAAAAGAUAGAAUGGACUUUUCAGGGUUGAACUAAAAUCUCUGCCUUCAAGGAGAUUGUAGUUCAAAGAGGCAAAAUGCUCAGCCACCAAAGUCCAGCAGGUUGUCAACAGACUGACUUUGGAAACUUUUCUAGACGAUAGAUAGAGAGAUAGACUGUGAUAUGAGAGGAAAGGAAGCCCUUUGCUAGGUCAUGGUUGCUAGUGAUACUUCACAGGUGCGAGAGGCCAGCUCUCCCUCCCCUCCAGCUGCGGGCAGGGGAGCAGAACAGAGAUGAUAUUGGGUCCUUCCAAGGUGGUUGGUGAGGGGGGUCUUCCUUUUAGUGCUCCCACAGCCCAGCAAGCAGUGGCCCCUCUCACAGGCCUGGUAGCAGGUCACCAUGGGGAGCUGGGGCCAGUGUGACUGUAAAGGGCAGCGUGACCUUCAUGCAGGCAGGCAGUCCUGCCAGACACACCCACAUGGCGUCUGUCCACCCUUGGCUGCACGGCCCGUGUUCUUACAUCUCAGAUGCCAAAGAAUUAAGAGUCUGACCUGGCCUCUCCGGGCCACUUCCCUAUGAGCACACAGCAGAGGAGACGGGGUCCUUAAGGGAUGGCAAGACACAAGAUUGUUCUCUGGGGCCGGACUGAGAAAUGCCUGAAGGAGACGACGGAGGAGAUCCGGCAGAUGGGCACUGAGUGCCAUUACUUCAUCUGUGAUGUGGGCAACCGGGAGGAGGUGUACCAGACGGCCAAGGCCGUCCGGGAGAAGGUGGGUGACAUCACCAUCCUGGUGAACAAUGCCGCCGUGGUCCAUGGGAAGAGCCUAAUGGACAGUGAUGAUGAUGCCCUCCUCAAGUCCCAACACAUCAACACCCUGGGCCAGUUCUGGACCACCAAGGCCUUCCUGCCGCGUAUGCUGGAGCUGCAGAAUGGCCACAUCGUGUGCCUCAACUCCGUGCUGGCACUGUCUGCCAUCCCCGGUGCCAUCGACUACUGCACAUCCAAAGCGUCAGCCUUCGCCUUCAUGGAGAGCCUGACCCUGGGGCUGCUGGACUGUCCGGGAGUCAGCGCCACCACAGUGCUGCCCUUCCACACCAGCACCGAGAUGUUCCAGGGCAUGAGAGUCAGGUUUCCCAACCUCUUUCCCCCACUGAAGCCGGAGACGGUGGCCCGGAGGACAGUGGAAGCUGUGCAGCUCAACCAGGCCCUCCUCCUCCUCCCAUGGACAAUGCAUGCCCUCGUUAUCUUGAAAAGCAUACUUCCACAGGCUGCACUCGAGGAGAUCCACAAAUUCUCAGGAACCUACACCUGCAUGAACACUUUCAAAGGGCGGACAUAGAGACAGGAUGAAGACAUGCUUGAGGAGCCACGGAGUUUGGGGGCCACAGCACCUGGGCACACACCCGAGCACCUGUCCAUUGGCAUGCUUCUGCUGGGUGAGCAGGACAGCUCCUGUCCCCAGCGAAGAAUCCGGCUGCCCCUGGGCCAGUCCCAGGACCUUUGCACAGGACUGAUGGGUAUAACUGACCCCCACAGGGAGGCAGGAAAACAGCCAGAAGCCACCUUGACACUUUUGAACAUUUCCAGUUCUGUAGAGUUUAUUGUCAAUUGCUUCUCAAGUCUAACCAGCCUCAGCAGUGUGCAUAGACCAUUUCCAGGAGGGUCUGUCCCCAGAUGCUCUGCCUCCCGUUCCAAAACCCACUCAUCCUCAGCUUGCACAAACUGGUUGAACGGCAGGAAUGAAAAAUAAAGAGAGAUGGCUUUUGUGA